AUUCUGCGAGGAAUGGCAGCGGCAGCAGCAUCCCCGCCAGAGGCGGCGGCGGCGGCGGCAGCGGCCACGGCCACCACCGCGGACGCUAUUGUUCCCUGGUGUUAGACGCGCUCUCCCUCCUUCUCAUCUGAAGCGAACAAUAGCAGGAAAGAGCUUUGCUUUCUGUACUCUUUGAAAAGACGUUCCAAGAGCGGAGAAAAAUUCCCUGCCGAGCGUGCUACGGCUCUGGACCCUGGAGUGGCUGCAGGCGGCAUGGGGCUGCAAGCCAGGCGCUGGGCGUCCGGGAGCCGGGGCGCUGCGGGGCCGCGCCGGGGCGUCCUGCAGCUGCUGCCGCUGCCGCUGCCGCUGCCGCUGCUCCUGCUGCUGCUGCUACGCCCGGGCGCCGGCAGGGCUGCGGCGCAGGGCGAGGCGGAGGCGCCCACCCUCUAUCUGUGGAAGACUGACAAAUGAAGAGUUACGUGGAUCUUCUCUUCUAUUUCUUUGCUCUUAAUUUUGAGGCACUGCUUAAGUCUUGCAUCAGAGUUAUCCAUAAGAAUUAAAAAAACGAAGAAGAAGAAGAAGAAGAAGAAGAGAUGAGGUCCAUGGGGCCGAUGUAUGGGAGAUGAAUGUGGUCCCGGAGGCAUCCAAACGAGGGCUGUGUGGUGUGCUCAUGUGGAGGGAUGGACUACACUGCAUACUAACUGUAAGCAGGCCGAGAGACCCAAUAACCAGCAGAAUUGUUUCAAAGUUUGCGAUUGGCACAAAGAGUUGUACGACUGGAGACUGGGACCUUGGAAUCAGUGUCAGCCCGUGAUUUCAAAAAGCCUAGAGAAACCUCUUGAGUGCAUUAAGGGGGAAGAAGGUAUUCAGGUGAGGGAGAUAGCGUGCAUCCAGAAAGACAAAGACAUUCCUGCGGAGGAUAUCAUCUGUGAGUACUUUGAGCCCAAGCCUCUCCUGGAGCAGGCUUGCCUCAUUCCUUGCCAGCAAGAUUGCAUCGUGUCUGAAUUUUCUGCCUGGUCCGAAUGCUCCAAGACCUGCGGCAGCGGGCUCCAGCACCGGACGCGUCAUGUGGUGGCGCCCCCGCAGUUCGGAGGCUCUGGCUGUCCAAACCUGACGGAGUUCCAGGUGUGCCAAUCCAGUCCAUGCGAGGCCGAGGAGCUCAGGUACAGCCUGCAUGUGGGGCCCUGGAGCACCUGCUCAAUGCCCCACUCCCGACAAGUAAGACAAGCAAGGAGACGCGGGAAGAAUAAAGAACGGGAAAAGGACCGCAGCAAAGGAGUAAAGGAUCCAGAAGCCCGCGAGCUUAUUAAGAAAAAGAGAAACAGAAACAGGCAGAACAGACAAGAGAACAAAUAUUGGGACAUCCAGAUUGGAUAUCAGACCAGAGAGGUUAUGUGCAUUAACAAGACGGGGAAAGCUGCUGAUUUAAGCUUUUGCCAGCAAGAGAAGCUUCCAAUGACCUUCCAGUCCUGUGUGAUCACCAAAGAGUGCCAGGUUUCCGAGUGGUCAGAGUGGAGCCCCUGCUCAAAAACAUGCCAUGACAUGGUGUCCCCUGCAGGCACUCGUGUAAGGACACGAACCAUCAGGCAGUUUCCCAUUGGCAGUGAAAAGGAGUGUCCAGAAUUUGAAGAAAAAGAACCCUGUUUGUCUCAAGGAGAUGGAGUUGUCCCCUGUGCCACGUAUGGCUGGAGAACUACAGAGUGGACUGAGUGCCGUGUGGACCCUUUGCUCAGUCAGCAGGACAAGAGGCGCGGCAACCAGACGGCCCUCUGUGGAGGGGGCAUCCAGACCCGAGAGGUGUACUGCGUGCAGGCCAACGAAAACCUCCUCUCACAAUUAAGUACCCACAAGAACAAAGAAGCCUCAAAGCCAAUGGACUUAAAAUUAUGCACUGGACCUAUCCCUAAUACUACACAGCUGUGCCACAUUCCUUGUCCAACUGAAUGUGAAGUUUCACCUUGGUCAGCUUGGGGACCUUGUACUUAUGAAAACUGUAAUGAUCAGCAAGGGAAAAAAGGCUUCAAACUGAGGAAGCGGCGCAUUACCAAUGAGCCCACUGGAGGCUCUGGGGUAACCGGAAACUGCCCUCACUUACUGGAAGCCAUUCCCUGUGAAGAGCCUGCCUGUUAUGACUGGAAAGCAGUGAGACUGGGAAACUGCGAGCCAGAUAACGGAAAGGAGUGUGGUCCAGGCACGCAAGUUCAAGAGGUUGUGUGCAUCAACAGUGAUGGAGAAGAAGUUGACAGACAGCUGUGCAGAGAUGCCAUCUUCCCCAUCCCUGUGGCCUGUGAUGCCCCAUGCCCGAAAGACUGUGUGCUCAGCACAUGGUCUACGUGGUCCUCCUGCUCACACACCUGCUCAGGGAAAACGACAGAAGGGAAACAGAUACGAGCACGAUCCAUUCUGGCCUAUGCGGGUGAAGAAGGUGGAAUUCGCUGUCCAAAUAGCAGUGCUUUGCAAGAAGUACGAAGCUGUAAUGAGCAUCCUUGCACAGUGUACCACUGGCAAACUGGUCCCUGGGGCCAGUGCAUUGAGGACACCUCAGUAUCGUCCUUCAACACAACUACGACUUGGAAUGGGGAGGCCUCCUGCUCUGUCGGCAUGCAGACAAGAAAAGUCAUCUGUGUGCGAGUCAAUGUGGGCCAAGUGGGACCCAAAAAAUGUCCUGAAAGCCUUCGACCUGAAACUGUAAGGCCUUGUCUGCUUCCUUGUAAGAAGGACUGUAUUGUGACCCCAUAUAGUGACUGGACAUCAUGCCCCUCUUCGUGUAAAGAAGGGGACUCCAGUAUCAGGAAGCAGUCUAGGCAUCGGGUCAUCAUUCAGCUGCCAGCCAACGGGGGCCGAGACUGCACAGAUCCCCUCUAUGAAGAGAAGGCCUGUGAGGCACCUCAAGCGUGCCAAAGCUACAGGUGGAAGACUCACAAAUGGCGCAGAUGCCAAUUAGUCCCUUGGAGCGUGCAACAAGACAGCCCUGGAGCACAGGAAGGCUGUGGGCCUGGGCGACAGGCAAGAGCCAUUACUUGUCGCAAGCAAGAUGGAGGACAGGCUGGAAUCCAUGAGUGCCUACAGUAUGCAGGCCCUGUGCCAGCCCUUACCCAGGCCUGCCAGAUCCCCUGCCAGGAUGACUGUCAAUUGACCAGCUGGUCCAAGUUUUCUUCAUGCAAUGGAGACUGUGGUGCAGUUAGGACCAGAAAGCGCACUCUUGUUGGAAAAAGUAAAAAGAAGGAAAAAUGUAAAAAUUCCCAUUUGUAUCCCCUGAUUGAGACUCAGUAUUGUCCUUGUGACAAAUAUAAUGCACAACCUGUGGGGAACUGGUCAGACUGUAUUUUACCAGAGGGAAAAGUGGAAGUGUUGCUGGGAAUGAAAGUACAAGGAGACAUCAAGGAAUGCGGACAAGGAUAUCGUUACCAAGCAAUGGCAUGCUACGAUCAAAAUGGCAGGCUUGUGGAAACAUCUAGAUGUAACAGCCAUGGUUACAUUGAGGAGGCCUGCAUCAUCCCCUGCCCCUCAGACUGCAAGCUCAGUGAGUGGUCCAACUGGUCGCGCUGCAGCAAGUCCUGUGGGAGUGGUGUGAAGGUUCGUUCUAAAUGGCUGCGUGAAAAACCAUAUAAUGGAGGAAGGCCUUGCCCCAAACUGGACCAUGUCAACCAGGCACAGGUGUAUGAGGUUGUCCCAUGCCACAGUGACUGCAACCAGUACCUAUGGGUCACAGAGCCCUGGAGCAUCUGCAAGGUGACCUUUGUGAAUAUGCGGGAGAACUGUGGAGAGGGCGUGCAAACCCGAAAAGUGAGAUGCAUGCAGAAUACAGCAGAUGGCCCUUCUGAACAUGUAGAGGAUUACCUCUGUGACCCAGAAGAGAUGCCCCUGGGCUCUAGAGUGUGCAAAUUACCAUGCCCUGAGGACUGUGUGAUAUCUGAAUGGGGUCCAUGGACCCAAUGUGUUUUGCCUUGCAAUCAAAGCAGUUUCCGGCAAAGGUCAGCUGAUCCCAUCAGACAACCAGCUGAUGAAGGAAGAUCUUGCCCUAAUGCUGUUGAGAAAGAACCCUGUAACCUGAACAAAAACUGCUACCACUAUGAUUAUAAUGUAACAGACUGGAGUACAUGUCAGCUGAGUGAGAAGGCAGUUUGUGGAAAUGGAAUAAAAACAAGGAUGUUGGAUUGUGUUCGAAGUGAUGGCAAGUCAGUUGACCUGAAAUAUUGUGAAGCGCUUGGCUUGGAGAAGAACUGGCAGAUGAACACGUCCUGCAUGGUGGAAUGCCCUGUGAACUGUCAGCUUUCUGAUUGGUCUCCUUGGUCAGAAUGUUCUCAAACAUGUGGCCUCACAGGAAAAAUGAUCCGAAGACGAACAGUGACCCAGCCCUUUCAAGGUGAUGGAAGACCAUGCCCUUCCCUGAUGGACCAGUCCAAACCCUGCCCAGUGAAGCCUUGUUAUCGGUGGCAAUAUGGCCAGUGGUCUCCAUGCCAAGUGCAGGAGGCCCAGUGUGGAGAAGGGACCAGAACAAGGAACAUUUCUUGUGUAGUAAGUGAUGGGUCAGCUGAUGAUUUCAGCAAAGUGGUGGAUGAGGAAUUCUGUGCUGACAUUGAACUCAUUAUAGAUGGUAAUAAAAAUAUGGUUCUGGAGGAAUCCUGCAGCCAGCCUUGCCCAGGUGACUGUUAUUUGAAGGACUGGUCUUCCUGGAGCCUGUGUCAGCUGACCUGUGUGAAUGGUGAGGAUCUAGGCUUUGGUGGAAUACAGGUCAGAUCCAGACCGGUGAUUAUACAAGAACUAGAGAAUCAGCAUCUGUGCCCAGAGCAGAUGUUAGAAACAAAAUCAUGUUAUGAUGGACAGUGCUAUGAAUAUAAAUGGAUGGCCAGUGCUUGGAAGGGCUCUUCCCGAACAGUGUGGUGUCAAAGGUCAGAUGGUAUAAAUGUAACAGGGGGCUGCUUGGUGAUGAGCCAGCCUGAUGCCGACAGGUCUUGUAACCCACCGUGUAGUCAACCCCACUCGUACUGUAGCGAGACAAAAACAUGCCAUUGUGAAGAAGGGUACACUGAAGUCAUGUCUUCUAACAGCACCCUUGAGCAAUGCACACUUAUCCCCGUGGUGGUAUUACCCACCAUGGAGGACAAAAGAGGAGAUGUGAAAACCAGUCGGGCUGUACAUCCAACCCAACCCUCCAGUAACCCAGCAGGACGGGGAAGGACCUGGUUUCUACAGCCAUUUGGGCCAGAUGGGAGACUAAAGACCUGGGUUUACGGUGUAGCAGCUGGGGCAUUUGUGUUACUCAUCUUUAUUGUCUCCAUGAUUUAUCUAGCUUGCAAAAAGCCAAAGAAACCCCAAAGAAGGCAAAACAACCGACUGAAACCUUUAACCUUAGCCUAUGAUGGAGAUGCCGACAUGUAACAUAUAACUUUUCCUGGCAACAACCAGUUUCGGCUUUCUGACUUCAUAGAUGUCCAGAGGCCACAACAAAUGUAUCCAAACUGUGUGGAUUAAAAUAUAUUUUAAUUUUUAAAAAUGGCAUCAUAAAGACAAGAGUGAAAAUCAUACUGCCACUGGAGAUAUUUAAGACAGUACCACUUAUAUACAGACCAUCAACCGUGAGAAUUAUAGGAGAUUUAGCUGAAUACAUGCUGCAUUCUGAAAGUUUUAUGUCAUCUUUUCUGAAAUCUACCGACUGAAAAACCACUUUCAUCUCUAAAAAAUAAUGGUGGAAUUGGCCAGUUAGGAUGCCUGAUACAAGACCGUCUGCAGUGUUAAUCCAUAAAACUUCCUAGCAUGAAGAGUUUCUACCAAGAUCUCCACAAUACUAUGGUCAAAUUAACAUGUGUACUCAGUUGAAUGACACACAUUAUGUCAGAUUAUGUACUUGCUAAUAAGCAAUUUUAACAAUGCAUAACAAAUAAACUCUAAGCUAAGCAGAAAAUCCACUGAAUAAAUUCAGCAUCUUGGUGGUCGAUGGUAGAUUUUAUUGACCUGCAUUUCAGAGACAAAGCCUCUUUUUUAAGACUUCUUGUCUCUCUCCAAAGUAAGAAUGCUGGACAAGUACUAGUGUCUUAGAAGAACGAGUCCUCAAGUUCAGUAUUUUAUAGUGGUAAUUGUCUGGAAAACUAAUUUACUUGUGUUAAUACAAUACGUUUCUACUUUCCCUGAUUUUCAAACUGGUUGCCUGCAUCUUUUUUGCUAUAUGGAAGGCACAUUUUUGCACUAUAUUAGUGCAGCACGAUAGGCGCUUAACCAGUAUUGCCAUAGAAACUGCCUCUUUUCAUGUGGGAUGAAGACAUCUGUGCCAAGAGUGGCAUGAAGACAUUUGCAAGUUCUUGUAUCCUGAAGAGAGUAAAGUUCAGUUUGGAUGGCAGCAAGAUGAAAUCAGCUAUUACACCUGCUGUACACACACUUCCUCAUCACUGCAGCCAUUGUGAAAUUGACAACAUGGCGGUAAUUUAAGUGUUGAAGUCCCUAACCCCUUAACCCUCUAAAAGGUGGAUUCCUCUAGUUGGUUUGUAAUUGUUCUUUGAAGGCUGUUUAUGACUAGAUUUUUAUAUUUGUUAUCUUUGUUAAGAAAAAAAAAGAAAAAGGAACUGGAUGUCUUUUUAAUUUUGAGCAGAUGGAGAAAAUAAAUAAUGUAUCAAUGACCUUUGUAACUAAAGGAAAUCAAAAUUAUAUGUUGAUUUUUCUUUCUCUCUGAUUUCCCAGUUUCAGAUUGAAUGUCUGUCUUGCAGGCAGUUAUUUCAAAAUCCAUAGUCUUUUGCCUUUCUCACUGGCAAAAUUUGAAGCAAUCUCUCUCUUCAAUGUAUGAUUUCAAAACUAAAAUUUUAAAAGAGAAGAAUAAAUAUCUUAUCCAAGACUUCAUUGCAUAUCUAGAGCAAGAGUGGCAAACUUUUUCUGUAAAGGACUAUAUAGAAAAUAUUUUCCACAAGGUCUAUGUUGCAACUUCUCAACUUUGCCAUUCUGCUAAUGCAAUCUUAGUAAAUAAAAGAAUGAACAUAACUGUUUUCCUAUAUAACUUCCCUUACAAAAACAGCCAGUAGGCCACCUUUGCAGGUCAUAUUUUGCUGACCCCUGGUCUGGAUGUUUUUUAAUGCUAGCUCUCCAUGGUGUCAUCUUUCGUUUUCAUUCAUUUUUCAAAGGUGAGAAUUUACAGUCAUUACAUUUCCCACUGUAUCAGAAGUAGCUGUAUUUUCUACAGAUGUAGCCCUGGGAAUGGCACAGUGGAACAAUAUUUAACUAACUCAGCAGACUUCUUGCAAAUGAAAAGAAAACUCAAAAGGUGCCAUUAAAAAGCAAUACCAUUUUCAGGCAACAUUAUUGCAACAACCUUUGUGAGAGAGGACACUAGCUUUUCAGGAUAUUUGAAAAAUAAUAUAACUAACAUGCUAUUUUAUCUUAAACAGCUGUGUUCCUGUAAAAGUGUUUUGGAUUAGAAGGUAUUUUUACCUUCAUACUGGAGUAUGAACUCCCCCUGCUGUUCAUUAGAGUAUUUGCAAAGAUUACAAAAGACAUCAGGUUAGGAUGUCAUUGUCCCCAAAAUGAAAAUAUUUGUAUGUAUUUCAAUAAGAACUAAAUGCAGUAAGCGCUAAUUCCUCAUUCAAUAUUCACUAUAUUAGGAAAUGUAAAUCAUUUCAAAGAGAACAGGUAGUCAGGAAGAUGAAAAUUUUACUUUAAAGCAAGGAUUUAAACAAAGAAAACCAUAAAAACAAAGUCCAUUUUAUCUGUUUUAUUAAAGAGGAAGAAAAAAUAAUAUUGUUACUUUAAAACUGUGAUUGUCAAUAUAUAUAAUCAGGGGUCUUCCAGAUAAUCCUAAAGUUGAUCUCUUUGAAUAAAAUAAACUCCAUUUGUCCAAAAUAGUUAAGAAAGACUCUAUUGUGGUUACUUGAAAAAUUCAGCUAACCCUCUUAUGAAAUGUGUGCAACACCUAUUAAUUUUGAAAUGUGGGAUAGAAUACCUACUAAAGCUAUAUUUAAGGUAUUGUAAAAUGUCAUUAAUUCAGAAAAGAUUAGUAUCAUCCUACCUAUAAGAAUUAAAUUAGCAAAUCAAAAUUAUAGAAUGUUAUGAAAAAUACAUUUUAUUCAUAAAUUAAUUAGAUUUUACAGCAUAUAUGCAUGCAUAUAUAUAUAUACACACACACACACACACACCCAUAUAUAUGAGAGAGAGGAAAUUAGGUUCAACAUGACCUAAUAUUAGAGAACAUAUUGGAAGGUCACUGUUUGUUAGGAUAAAUAAAUACUGGAUAACCUCGUUAGAAAGGUGGAAAGAGGAGAACGUAGCAAUCUGGCUAUUUUGGACAAAGGGAAGGUUAUUAUAUUCAUGUUUAUAACAUGAAAAUGGCCUUAUUUUUGUUUCUGACAUGAGACAAUAAUGAGUUAAAUAUUUUAUUGGAAUUUCAUCAAAACCUUAUUUUUACUGUUCCUUCUAAAAAUUUGGGAGGGGAAUAUAGUAGUAACUUCUCUAUUGACACUUUUACCUCACCGAGGGGGUAAAAGAUGUAGAACUGCUGUUCCCUAGAAUGAAGGUCUGUUGUUUGGUUUUUAAAAAAAGAAGAGCAGAAAAAGUUUGACACAGUAUUAUAUGAUUUUGCUGGACUAUUUCACUAGAAACCACGUAGAAUAGGACUAACUGAUCUCUUUUGAAAGGGGCUGAUUUGCUUAUUCAUCAAUAACUAAUCCAAUAUGUGGACAGUAAUCUUAAUUUCAAAGCCUUUUUUGAGGAUACUACGGUGUAGCUUAAGUGAAUUUAAAAAGAGUGCAUAAAAGCUUGUUUUUAAUUACUUAUAACAAAGCACAAAUUACUUCUAACAAGGCAAAUAUUUAUUGACAUAUAAGACAUUCUGCUAGGCAUUGUAAAAAAAAAAAAAAAAGUAAUGGCUUUUGUAUACAUAGGUACUUAAGACAGACAUCCAAAAGAAGGAAAAAAUGCUUAAUGAGUGAAGAUAGCACUGAAACAUGUUGACUUUUACUCUAGGUUUGUUUUUAGAUGGGGUUAGUAUUUUCCCCUACGUAAUGUACAUGUCUUUAGGCCACAGUAUUAGGAGUUUGAUUUUUCCCUGCCCCACCCUCAGGUAGGUGGCAGUGGUCAUUGUAGCUUAAUCAGACCCCUGUUAAGUUCCUGGGCAUUUCAAGGUAAAUUCACGUCUUCCUUCUCACAGAAAUUGAAUAGACCUCUCACACACUUAUUUACCUCCCCCAACAACCUGUAUCCUUGGCCCUUUCUGAUUUUCUCUGCUUGGUCUCUUUCUACUCUUGACAGCUAUUCUUACCUACUUCCCACUAAACAUGCCCAAUUUUUUAAUUAAAAAAAAAAGAAUUCCUAUAUUUCCUUCCCUAUUAGAAUCAAAGUGUCACUCACUCAGAGUGUGAACAUCCUGAUUUACACCAAAUCCACUGGUCAAAGAAAUGAAUAAAGGGAAAAGGAAAAAUGUGGAAGGCAUGCAGGAAAAAAAAAAAAAAAAAAGCCCUUUUCUGUAAAAAUGUCCAUGCCUACACUUGCUUUAGACCAUCCCAUAUCCUCCUGCCUCCAUCUCGAGUCUUUGUUCACAUUCCACACCACAAGACAGUGAGGGAGGACUGUACUUUUCAGUACCAUACAGAAGGGAGAGCCUGUUCUAAAGCUGACGUGGGUCUCAAUAGUACAUGAGAAGCACAAUUCCCAAAUGAUCUGGGAUCUCCUGUUUAUAAAUAUAUUACCAAAUUCAAGUGUGGGUUCUUCUUCUAUUUCCACUGUAAGAUUGAGGGUGUUGAAAAAACAGUAGUCCUUGAGCAAAUCUGUGAGGAAUCUUGUCAGAAUGUGAUCUUUCCUGGGACUAGUUUAGUUGUGAGAACUACAUCUGCUUGUUCUGGGAAUAAGGGUCUCCCCAGGUCCUGCCCUCAGGUGGCCCUGGCUGCAGGACAGGAUUUCAGGUAUCAGAAACUGGUGUGUGAGCCAAGCAAAUAGUUAUCCAUUUAUAAAAAGGAUGGUUUGCAGUGUGUUAUAAUAAUUUUAUAUCUAGCAGGGACAAUGAAAAAUGGUUAUGUCUACAUUAUUAAAUGAAUGAAACUAAUGCUAAACAGUUAAUUUUGCAUUUUUAUUUUUCUGUGUUUCUACCAAGUCAGAUCUUAAAAAUGGGCAGUAUAUGAAGAGCUUUAGUUUGUGGGAGUCAUGUUUUCAGUGAUCAAAAAUCUCUAUAUUAUUUAGAAUAUAAUUGUCAGUCUUGUUGUGUUUUGUAGAUUUAUUGUUUUUAAGCCAUAGUUUCUAGAUUACCUACUUUUAACCCUCAAGUAAACUUUUCCCUAUUUUUCAGAAAUCUGUUUGUGUUUAUUUUUAGAAAGUAAACAUUUAGAUUCCUUUUCUGGUACUUUUUUUCUCCAUUUCUAUCACACAGAUUUGAAGAGAUCAGUAUCUAUCAUUGUAAAAUAUAACUUUAUUAAAAUUUGCAAUCUGUCUUUCUAUAAAUUAUUAUUCCCUAAAUGUGUAUUUUAUGUUAAUUUAACUACCUGAAUAUUUAUUUUGUUUAAAUAAGGAGGCAGCUGUCUAAGAAUUUUUGUUAAUAUUACUUUGUAAAUUGCGUAAUGUAAUUUAUUUUACAUUAUGUACAUUUCCUUUUUAACGCACAAAAUGUCUAUGUACAAUUAACUACAGAUUUGCAAAUAAUGUCACUAAGCUUUAUUCAGUCAAUACAGAUGGCAUGUGAAGAUGUAAUAUGCUUUUUUACAUUUUCAUAUGGGUUAUUUGUAAAUAACUAUAUUGCUGACAAACAUAAAUACGGAAAUCAUUUUCAUUCUAAUCAUGUGUAUCUGUGUUUUGAUUUGCACCAAUUGCUUCUUAAAUAUGGAUUAAAAUUUUUUUCCAGUGAA